AUGAACCCUCGUUGGAGGGGCAGCCCCCGAGGCCCACGAUGCUCGGCCCAGUGCUCUCCCCGAGCGGCCCGCAGCGCGCCCACGACCCCGCGCGGUGCGAGCCCACCUCCCGCCGGGGCUGGGGACGGUGGGGAGGGAGGGUAUUACCGGAGGGCCGCCGCCGCCGCCGCUGCCGCCGCGUCCCAGCGCUGGUGGCUGCUGCAGCAGCCCGGCUCUGCUGGAGGGUCCGUGCGGCGUGGUGUAGAGGAGGCUGCCGGCGGUCUGCUCCGCGCCGGGGGCACUGGGGAGGAGGGGGCCGGCGGCUACGGCGCCGCUUUGGAGGGAGGAGGAACAGGAGGUGGUGGAAGUCGGCGGCGGCGGCGGCGAAGCCGGGGCUGGCUAGCAGUGCCCUUUUGUCCAUGGAGGCUGCAGCGGCGGCGGCGACGACAGCCGCCCCCUCCCCACCCCCGGCGGUCACCAGUCGGAGUUUCCAAGUCUCUCCUCCUUCUCUCCUCCCCGCCCGGCGCUUCCGAGCCCCCUCUCUCUCUUUUCUUUUUAUUUUUCCGCACCGCACAGGCCCCGGGGGCCAAAAAUAAUCGGGGCUCUGGAGAGAGGAGGGUCCCGGCCGCACGGAUAUCGGGCCCCAAGCGGGGAUGGAGGCGUCGGGGGCGGCCGAUGCAACGGAUUGCGAGGCGGCGGCGGCAGCCCGGGUGCUGCGGCCGGCAGCUGAAAAAUGGCUCCAGGAAGCUGCUGCUGACAAUGAAUGAAGGGAUACGGUUUACGCGCCAAGGUCCUCCCGCGAAACUCGGAUUUCCCGCCGGCUUUUCAAACCAUAUUUGCAUAUCCCCGCCCCUCAACCCGCCGAGGACCGUUCCCACAGCCCAUUGGGCCGCUACCUCCUUACUUCAGUCCCAAUCAUGGAGCAGGGCCGCGACUUGCUGGUUUCCAUUGGCUGCCGUGCAUCAUGGUUACCGGGGCGACAGGGACCCUAUUUGCAUAGGCCUCCUUGAUUGGCUGGCAGAAGAGCAGUUUUUAGGGGGUGGGGCAAAGAAUUUCCUUCUCUCCCACGGAAGACCACGCCUGGCCUAGGCUCCGCCCCUGUCCCCGCCCGCCCGCCGGGCCGGCGCUACUGACCUGGGCAGGGACUCCGCGCCCCGCAGACUCAGUGUAGAUCUAGUCUAGAGCCCAAGUUUCGCUUUUGGAAAUUGUCAAGGUGACUAAGGGAACACUCUUUCCUUUGACCAGUCAGUGCAAUAAACGAACAGCGCAGGAGAUUUUUCCAGAUACGUGCCAAAGGCAAGUUGGACCAUGCGGACGAUGUCUGGCAGGUGCAAAAGGAGCCCUUUAAAUCGUGGGCUUCUCCCUUCCUGAAAUCCAACCAAUGACGCGGCGAGAGCUGAUCCCGAGGCCGGGGCUGAUAGACAGAAGCAUGUGGGCAGACAGAAUCGUGGGGGCAGAAGGUUCAGCAGACGCGAUUGCGGGCACCAGUUAACAUUCCAGAUCAUUCCCGGUACCUUCAUUAUUAGCCUGGAUAGGGGUAAAGUACAAAUUAACUCUUUUGUCUUACAACGGAUAUUGGUUUGAAUCCAGCAGACAUUCCCUCUGGCCCAGAAACACCCAGGGCAGUUAAUCAGGGCUAACCUAGAACUGAUCUACGGGUUUCUAAUCCGCCAAGCAGUAAUCCGAAAAAGUACACGCUUCCCACGAUGACGUCGUGCCCCCAACGAACGCAGGCACGCCCAGGCAUCAGCACUUUAUAUCUUCAGUUUUGUAGGAAGUUCUCUGACUGGAAGCAAACACAACGACUCAAACCUAUCCCAAAGUAUUUUUAAAAUAGUGUCUUUUUUUAAAAAGUAAACUAGAAAUUGUCAUCAGAAAAAUAUAAAAUGAUGUGUCAAACUGA